AUGGAAAAUUACAAUCAAACAUCAACUGAUUUCAUCUUAUUGGGGCUGUUUCCACCAUCAAGAAUUGACCUUUUCUUCUUCAUUCUCAUUGUUUUCAUUUUCCUGAUGGCUCUAAUUGGAAACCUGUCCAUGAUUCUUCUCAUCUUCUUGGACACCCAUCUCCACACACCCAUGUAUUUCCUACUGAGUCAGCUCUCCCUCAUUGACCUAAAUUACAUCUCCACCAUUGUUCCUAAGAUGGCAUCUGAUUUUCUGCAUGGAAACAAGUCUAUCUCCUUCACUGGGUGUGGGAUUCAGAGUUUCUUCUUCUUGGCAUUAGGAGGUGCAGAAGCACUACUUUUGGCAUCUAUGGCCUAUGAUCGUUACAUUGCUAUUUGCUUUCCUCUCCACUAUCUCAUCCGCAUGAGCAAAAGAGUGUGUGUGCUGAUGAUAACAGGGUCUUGGAUCAUAGGCUCGAUCAAUGCUUGUGCUCACACUGUAUAUGUACUCCAUAUUCCUUAUUGCCGAUCCAGGGCCAUCAAUCAUUUCUUCUGUGAUGUCCCAGCAAUGGUGACUCUGGCCUGCAUGGACACCUGGGUCUAUGAGGGCACAGUGUUUUUGAGUGCCACCAUCUUUCUCGUGUUUCCCUUCAUUGGUAUUUCAUGUUCCUAUGGCCAGGUUCUCUUUGCUGUCUACCACAUGAAAUCUGCAGAAGGGAGGAAGAAAGCCUAUUUGACCUGCAGCACCCACCUCACUGUAGUAACUUUCUACUAUGCACCUUUUGUCUACACUUAUCUACGUCCAAGAUCCCUGCGAUCUCCAACAGAGGACAAGGUUCUGGCUGUCUUCUACACCAUCCUCACCCCAAUGCUCAACCCCAUCAUCUAUAGCCUGAGGAACAAGGAGGUGAUGGGGGCCCUGACACGAGUGAGUCAGAGAAUCUGCUCUGUGAAAAUGUAG